AUUGUAAGCUGUGUAGAAGAGAAGGUAUCAGCCAUAUUUUUCCUUUUAGGCAGAGUUUGAUUUGCAGAGGCCUGGACUUCCUGCUUAUGUGUCUUUCCAGUGAAUAAGUGUGAUUCACCACAGUUCAAAGUAACCCCAUCUACAACGCCUCAUUUUUUUAAGUGAAAUUUUUCCAUGGGAAUAGAAUAGAGAGGAAUCCUGUAGGUCUUCCAUGAAAUUAUACUCCCUGCCUCUCAGAGUUUUACAAUAUAAUUAGGUUACUUGUUUGUCUUAAAUUUUUUUAUUAUCCUGUGCUUAUCUGGUUGAGGUGCCUGUUGAAGAGCAGGAGAUGAAGGUCAAGAAAUAUAAGCACAGUGCUCAAUUUUUUAAAAUAACUUUGUCUUACUGUUGCUCGUGGAUAGAAAUAAAAUUUUUCAUAUUAAACUAAUACUUAGCCGUUUGCUGAAACCUCUUAUCAAUUCUAAUAAUUUAUCUGUAUUCUCUUAGUUUUUCUGUGUAACAGACAUACCAUCUAUAAAUAAUUACAAGUUUUUGUUCUUUUUCAAUCUUUUAUCUUUUAUAUAUUUAUUUUUUCUUUUCCUACCACUCUGGCUAGGACCUGCAGGAAAUAGCACAGGGGAUAGGAAGUAGGGAUAGCGGGGAUAGGAAGUAGGGAUAGCACAGAUCCUUAGCUUGUUACUGAUUUUAAAGGGAAGGCUGUUAGCAUUUCACCAUUGAGUAUGGUGCUUACUGCUGGGUUUUGGUAAAUACUUUCUAUUAGAUUAUGAAAGUCCCCUUCUGAUCCUAGUUUGCUAAAAGUUUCUAUUUUAAAAAAUUAUAAAUGUGUUAAUUAUUACUGAGUGCCUUUUCUGUAUCUAUUGAUAAGAUCAUUGGGGUUUUCUCUUUUAAUCGGAUAGUACAGGAAUUAUUGUCAUCCAUUUUUUAAAGUUAAAUCAUCCUUGCAUUAUUAGCAAAAAUCCACAUUAGUCGUGAUAUAUUUUAUGCAUUGUUGGGUUCUGUUUGCUGAUAUUUUAUUUAGGAUUUUUACAUUUGUAUUUAUAUCUGAGAGUGGUCCAUAAUUUUCCUUUUUCCUACCAUCUUGGAUUUGGUUCUGAGAUAGUCCUAGUGCUUUUCCAUUUUCUAUCUCCUGCAUUUUUUUUUGGUUUUGAUCUAAAACACAGAUUUUUUUUUUACUUUUUUUUCUCUAAAACCAUCUGAACCUAGUGUUUAUUGGUUUUUGGAUUUUUUUGGGUGGAAGGAUGAGAAGCUUUUUAACUAAUGAAUCAGUUUUUUAAAGGUUAUUAGACUAUUCAGGUUUCUGUCUUGUUAGAAUAAUAAUUUGAAUUUUUCUGUGAUAUUCUUCAUUUCAUUGAAAUUUUCAAACUUAAUGGCACAUAUUUCUUCAUAGUAGUGUGCUGUUAUUUAAUCCUUGCUGAAUCUGUAGUUAUGUUCUCUCAUUCAUUCCUAAUGUUAUUAUUUGUAACAUCUCUGUAUUUUUCUUGAUCAGAUUUGGCUCUUAUUAGUCUUUCCAAAUAAAUAGCUUUUCCUUUGUUCAUCUUCUCUAGUGUAUCUUUGUUUUCUGAUUUUAAUUUCUACCCUUUAUUAUUUUCUUCUUCUGCUUUCUUUGGAUGUACUCUUAUUUACUUUCUGACUUCCUGAGUUGGAUACUUGUUCAUUAAUUCUCAGUCCUUUUUUCUUUCUAGGACAAGAUUUAAGUAUUUUAUUCUAAAUAAAACUGUAGUGAAAUCUGAUAUAUUCUAAUAUGGAGUAUUUUUAUCAUCACUCAGUUAUAAGAAUGUUGUAAUUACCAUAAUUAUUUCUUCUUUGAUUCAUGAGUUUUAUUAGCAGCAUCAUUUUGAAUUCCCAAAUGAAUGAGAGUCUUUAGUAAUCAUUUUGUUACGGAUUUCUAACUUAAAAAAUCUGUUGUGGUCUGGGAAUGUUGUUUGUAUGAUACUAUUUCCACAAAAUGCAUUGAGACUUGGUUUGUGGCCUAGGACAUGGUCAAUUCUUUUUAAAUAUUCCGUGAAUUUCUUUAGUGCAUAUUCUCCGAUGGGGGCUGUGGGGACAGAGUUCUAAAUAUGCCCAUUAGAUUAAAUCUCUUCAUUCUGUUGCUCACAUCUUCUAUAUCCUUAUUAAUCUGUCAAUCUCUUCAAGAGAGGUGUUAUUAAAAUCUCUCACUGUAUGUGUCACUUUGCCCUUAAAAUUCUGAUGAUUUGCUUUAUAAAUGGUUAUAACCAUUUUCCAGGAAGAACAUUAAAGAACUUUCCAUUGGCAUUAUCCAGUUUCCCUCAAAAUACUGGUUUUUUUUAUUUUGGCUUCUAAGCAGCUAUGAAUCCAGUUUCUCAGAAGCCCUUGUCUCAAGGCAUUUGUUUCCAGAUUACCUUGUUAGCAUCCACACUAUGGGCUAUUUUAGAAAAACAAAAAAAGUAUCAAAAUCAUAUAGCUAUGAUUUUCCUGUGCUUGAAGGAGCCUUAAAGCUCAUCUAGUCCAGCCAGUAUUUGUUCAUCCAAAUUCUGCCAAGAAAUCUCUAUUGUCAAGAUAUUCUUUACCAUCUUUGGGACAUUCUCAUUAUUAGAAACAAAUCCUAAGAAGAAAUUCUGCCAUAUACAACCCAUCCGUUCUUUAAAAAAAAAAAAAAAACAGCUUAAAUUUUCUUGUCUAAGCACAACAAUUUCCAGUGUUUGUAUUAGUUUUUCUCAACAGAAUUUCGAGUCCUUUUAACAUCGUAUUACUGUUAACAAGUUCUAAAUUCUGUGUGGUCAUGCUUUGAGAGACUGUCAGAUUAUACACACACACUCAGGUUGUGUGUGUGUUUGUGUGUUUGUGUUAAGGAAUGUUUUAGUGGGCACCUAUUAAGGAAGCCUCUCAGGAAACUACUGUAUAUUAAGGCCAAAACCAACUGAACCCAUCAUACGAUUUCUCUCCCUCAAGGAAAGCAAAUGAGAAUGAGCGACUGUAACCCUUGCCUGUUGUUCAUAAGCAUGUACACCAGGAUCUGUGUGAUCCUUUUCCUGAAGAUAAACAGCAUACUGCUCAAGGAAGGAAAACAACGCAUAGCAACAAAUUUCCUGUUUUUUAAAGAAAGAUCCAACUUGGUUUAGAAAUUAUGCUGGCUUGCUUUCUAUGUUUCUAAUAGAGAAUAAGGAGAAACUUGCUUCUCAUUUGCCGACAUGAGGAGAAAUCAUGCAGUCUUCCUAGAGGUCUCCAUCAUAAGCGAGUUUUCCAUCAUGUAGGUCAUUUAUCCCUGUCAUUUCUUAAUUCCAUAUUUGUUUCCACACACAGAUUUUGAACAUAUAUUUUGAACAUAUAUUUAUUUAAAAUAUUUGUUUUUAUCUAGCAUUGUGCUGAAAGUUUUACCCUAUUAUAAUUGUGUUAUCUACAUUUAAGUUUUUUACCUUUUAAGGAAAAGAAAAAGGAGAAACUCUACAAUCAUGCAAAAAGUAUAUAAUUUGCCUGGGAGAUGCAGAAUAACUUCUAGCAGAUAAUUACAUGCUUUGAACAUGAAAAGAAAUAGGGUAGAACCUGAACUAAAAGAGGACCAGGUUCUGUUCUCCCUCCCUCAGGGGAGGAUAUUUUAGAAUAUUUUGUGUUCAUGUUUUAAUAAGCUUUUGUUGGAUUAUUAAGGUGCAUUUAAGUUUUUCCAUCUUAGAAGUAUUCGGCUGGUGCAAAAGUAAUUACCAAUUACUAAUAUAAUCUUGUCAAGUAAAACCCACUCAUUGGGGUACAUAGAGCAAGCAUCCUCUUUUCCGUAGGGCAGCUCAGUCUGUGUAUCAUAAACAUGAUUAUCAUUGCCAUUCAAUUUUAGCUGUUGCUCCAGAGAGACUUAAAGGCAUGUCACAUGUGAGAGAUCAGCAGGCAAUAUUUGGGGCUAUGAAUAUUGAGCAAAUAUUAAGGUUUUUUUAAAGUUCACCUUCACUCAUGAUUUACCUGCCCUAAGGAAUUUGCCACAGAUUCCAAAUGUCAGCACUAGAAGAAGUGUCCGAGAUGAUCUGGAUGAACCAUUAUAGUGACUGAGGCCCAGGAAGAGUGAGUGGUUUACCUUAGGUAACCAGCAGGUCAGGGUAGAAUGCAUGUUUCUGUUCAGUCAUUUUAUUCACCUCCUAGGAAACAUAUUGCAGUGCAGUUGGUUUGCCACUUUUGAUCAAAUGCACCAAAUCUUCAAUUUGGAUUAAUCUUUUCAAUUACUGAGUAUACCGGUCCUUUCCCAUAGACUUAGAACAAACUACAAAUGCAGGCAACACAGGUAAUUAAUUUUAAAUUACCGAGUAGCCACAUUUAAAAAGCAAAAAGAAACACAUGAAAGUAAUGUUAAUAUUUUUAAAUUUAAGACGACCUGUGUAAAAUAUUAUCAUUUCAACAUGUAAUCAUAUUUUAAAAUUUAUUAAACAUUUUACAUUCUUUUUUCAUGCUGUCUUUGAAACCUGGUUAUAUGCUUUAUACUUACAUUACAUCUCAUCUUGAACCAGCCACAUGUGGUUAGUGCUUGCUUACCCUAUUAGCACAGGUCUAUAUGGAUGAACAGGUCCAAGCUCUACACCAAACCACAGGCCCCUAACCCUUGAGAUCAAAAAUGUCUCUGAGUACUAGUUCCCAUUUCUUUGAAUUUUUGCUCUUGAUACGCCAUGCAUGUCUCCUGAAAACCCAGAGAGGUGAGCAAGCAUGAACUGCUAUAAAAUGAGUGUGUCUGUUGAAAACAUGGUCCAGCUCCUGCUAAGAUAGCGUCAUUCUGUGAUACAAUAUUCCUGUCUUCAUCUAAUUCCAUGAAGUUCUGCAUUUCCUUAAUGUCAAAAGUUCCCUUACCAGCUGCAGCCGUUUCCUGUGGAUAAUGUUCUAAAUGGCUUUUAUUUAUGAGAUGUCUUGUGCUAUAACUGCUAUCAGAAUGAAUGUGUAUUCCAAAACCUAUUCCCCAAGUCAGUCUAAUUAACAAUCUUCUAAGAAAUAAUUGUUAAACUUCAGCUGUAGCUCACAACACGGGUAUGUCUCGCUUUGACCUAAUUACAGAAUGUAAUGUUAAAAUAUGUAAGGAAGGAGAUCAAAGAGGAAAGUCAUUUUGCUUUCUAUGUCUUCAUCUUGCUUUCUAUGUGCCUCAUAUUUCACAGCUCCCAACCUCCACUUCCAACUGGCUGAGGGAAGGAAACACAUGGAAUAGUAAUGAAUGAGUAUAGACGCUGAGGCUGUUUUAUUUUCCUCAUCUUUGAAGCAGGAACAAUAAUAGUGCCUAUCCUGGAGAUUCGUAAGAAUGAAGCAUGAAGCAUGGGAUCUGACAUAUCGUUGAUGCUCAACAAAUAUUAAAUUGCUUCAGAAAAAUAGCAAAUAGGUAUAUCUGGUGCGAAAAAUGGAAAGGAAGCCUGCCAGCUUUUUUUAAGGACACUAUCUGCAUUAUUCUUGGAAUUGAAUCCGGCUCCACCCAGGGCUGAGAGCUUUUCGUUUCCAUUGUGUCUUUAGCAUAGCCAUGCAAACCAACAUCACUUCCAAUGAUAGGGGAAUGCUGGAGUCAAAGCGACUAGUUCACUUCAGAGGACAGGCAGUGUAUAAUGUCAGGGGGAGGAGCUGACCCAAAUAAUGUGUUUCAAGUCAUCAGAACACGUUCAUGUCUGGUUUUCAUAGUAAAUUGUGACAGCUGCGCAGGAGAAGACAGAAUACACUUUUUAGAUGUUAUUUUGUUUAUUUUGUGAUGCUGCUUUAAACAGUUCCACAGAGUAAGGAAAUGGAGUUUUUACACUGUGAGACUUUAACUCCCUUCUUUCCUUGACUUGCCUCUUGGCUCUGCUUAAUAAGCCCUUUCAGCAAGACCUCAUCUGCUUUCCUUGAAGCUUCCAGGUAUUAUCUCUUGGUUGAAUAUAACAAAAAUCACACCAAGUAGCUACCUGACACUCAUGGGUGCAAGUAUCUCAUAGGAAACUGGUGAAUUCUGAAAAUGCUUUUGAGCCACUUCCUUUCACUGCUGGACUCUCUUAAUCUACUUACUAAAGUGCUACUUGGACAAGAGAGUAUUGACAGUUACAGGGAAAAACAAUGUAGAAUCCCAGGCCAUGUGUAGGUUUCUGUGGACACAUUUUAAUUUUUUAAAGAAUAUUUUAGUUAUCUAAAUUAUGUACCUAACCAUUUAUAUUGAGUACAUAAAUUCUCAGUAAAUUAGCGUCUCUCUUUUGAGGGCUGUGUGUUAUCUGCUCCUGUGAUCCAAAUAUAUAGCACUAAGACAAUAUAAGGGAUUCUCUCUCUCUCUCUGUCUCUCAUUCUCUCUCUCUCUUCCUUCCCCCCUUCCUUUCUCUCCCUGCCUCCCUCCCUCUACCCUCUCUCUGUUUGUCCUAAUUUACCUGACGUUUUAGCCCUUGUUGCUGUUGGAGGAUUCUAAAGAUGAAGCCACUCAUAACCUUAAUGCCUGAUAGCAUAGAGAAUAGUUGGUGACUUCACCAGAACUUACACACCCAUGCCUUUUCUUUUUUGCUUUGCCAUGAGUAGGCAGUUGCAUACUUUAUUUAGCAAAAGAGAGAACUGUUAAAAAGCUACUAAGUAGUGGUAUAUUCAUACCAUGGAAUACUACUAGGCAAUAAAAGCUACUAUAAUGGAUAAAGCAAUAAAAACUACUAUGCCACUCAGCAGCAAUAAACUACUGAAUAUACAAUAUCAUGGACAAAUGUCAAAAACUUGCCACAUAAAAUAAGUAGACACAAAGAAUACAUACUGUAUGAUUACCUUUAUAUGAAACCCUAGACCAGAGAAAACUAAUCUGUCGUGGUAGAAAUCACAACCGUGUUUGCCUGGGAUGGAAUUGACUACAAAGGGACCCCAGUGCAUCUUUCUAGGGUGAUGAAAAUGUUCUAGAUCUUGAUGGGGGUUUAGAUUAUACAGGUAUAUACGUUUGUCAGAACUCAUUGAACUGUAAACUUAAAUCUGUUUAUACAUUGCACUGUGGAUAAAUUAUGCCUAAACUUUAAAAAAAAGAAGAGGGAACUAAAAAAUCCACACGCCUUGCUAAACCUCCUCAAAUUAUUAGAAAUUCUCUUUCACUUAUGAACUAUUUUCUUGAAAGACAGCUACCAGGUAUCACUAUCACCAUCUUUUUGUACCAGGUACGUGGGUUCCUUUCAGACUCUUCCUGGUGCUGCAAUACACAGUGGUCACCCACAUUUGAGAAACAUACAGUGCCUUCCUUUUCCCAGGAGAUUAUCCCAGAGUUACAUGGGAAAUCAAUGUUGUAUAAGUUGCACAGGGGAAACAUUACUGAAGGCAUUUUUUUGGAAGGUAUAAGUGUAUUCACUCCCCAGUGUAUUGUGGGCUGUGUUAAUUCAGAAUUUGGAAGAGAAUGCUCUUAAGCCAGGAUGUUUUGUAAAGUGUUCUGUGUUGCAAUGUGCAGAUGUUUACAUCAAAUUUUAAAUCUUUCACUUACCUGCUCACCUUCUCCCUCCAGAACAUGCUGCCUGUUGUUAAGCACUGUUUCUGAAAUACAAAUCCAUUGUGCAACUCUUGCUCAGAAACUACAGUGGCCUGCUCCCUCCUUCACAUUUGGGCCCUGCUUAACUCUCUAGUUACCUGCAUUCGCUCAUUCUUGGCUUGUGUCACACCAAACAAAGCUGCUCCCUGGCAUGCUCCUCUCUCCUGAAUCCAUGCCUUUGUAAGAGCUGUUCUGCAGCCUGCAAAGCACCCUGCCCAUCCCCUUGCGCACCCCCUUUUUCACCAGUCCUUCCCACAGGCCCCACUCAGAUGCCCAUCCUCUGAGAACCCAUCCCAGCUUUUGCAGGAGGGAUGAGUCACAUGCCCAAGCUUCAAGAACACUGUAUGUGUUUCUUCAGGCAAGCAGGCUUACUACAUUGGAGAGAACAGGUCCUUUCCUUGUCUGCCUUCUCCCAUGGGCUGGACACCCUUCAGUGAAAGAGAUGGCAUUCGCGUCUGUAUUUUGUGCACACUGCUUGGAUACAUAGUAUUUGCCCAUGAAUGAUGGGUGAAUGGGUGGGUAGGUGGAUGGAUGGAUAGAUUCAUUCACUCACUCACUCAUUCAUUCAACACUGCAGCAGUAGCCUUCUUUGUGGGACCACCAAAGAGGAGACAAAUAAGAACCAGAAUGUUGUGUGGCCCUAGCAAAAGCAGAUUUUUCUGGGCGGAUGUUAAAGUAUUCCAGUCCCACUUUCCUUGCUUUAUUUUUCCAAGCAAUAAGGAGAACAUGACAAUAUUCUUUGCCGGGGUUGUACUUUCUACCUCUCCUCUGCAUAAGGGUAUUCCUACCUAAUUCUAAGAGAAAAAAUGAAAACUUACCACUAAUGAUAUAAAAAGCAUAUUUAUUGUUAGGUGAUAUUUGUAUUUUGGGGGUUUUUUCCUCACUAGGAAAAUUUUCUAAAUACCUUUGCAUAUACCACUUUGUUUUAUCUUUACAAAAAUCUCAUUAAUUAAGCAGGGGAUGGAUCAUCAUUCCCACCAGGCAAAUGAGAUAACUGACGUGUAGUAAAAGCCUGAUGAUUUUUCCAAAGUUACACAUCUGGUUAGUGAUAAUGCUGGGACCAGAAUAGGAGUCCAUGUGUUCCCACCAGACUGGGAGAUUGUUCCAAAGAACAAGUUCCCAGGAAAGAUCAAAUAAUUGCUGGAAAAGCACUUCCGAUCUCCAGCAAAAACAGAUCUUUCCAGCUGAGUGCCCUCCCUAAGGCCUGAAGAGUAUUAUCUGCCAAGUAGCUAUUCUUUUGUCUUCUGCAUAAACCACUGCAGGCUGAAGGCCACUGUGAAAUCUGUGAGAAUCAAGAGCAGCCAUCCACUGCAGAAAUAUAUGUUAUGAAACUUAAGGAAUAAGUCACUGUCCAUCCAGAGAGAAAUUAGAGAAUGCCUUUUCUGAAAUCUCUGCUAGGACACAGGUGUGGGCCCUAACGCAGAUAUGAAGCUUUGUCCCCAGUGCUAAGACGAGACAGCUAUUUUUGCUGGGCCAAUGUAAUAUUUAAAAGCAAACAUUUAACAGUAGGAUAACGGCUGCUGAAGCUGCAUUUGCAGCUGCAGCUGCAUCAUUCCUCUGGGGAAGGCAAGAUGGCUCUUCUCCAGCUAUUCAUGAAGGGCAAGAGUUGGGAGCAGAAAGAGAAUUUGCUCAUACGUAAUACUGUGCGGUCCAAUCUCAUGUCCCAUGUGAGAUGCCUAAGUCAGAAGCUGACUGCAAAGACAGCUCAUCGGCUUGGAGACCCAGGGUUCAUUCUGCAAGAUCUUUCAGGCCACUUUUUUUCUAUAAUAAAUGAAAUCCUUUGCAUUUUAUUGGGAGUAAGAGAGCCAGAUCUUUUCAGACAUUAACAAAUGAGGGGCCGUGAAUGUGGUCCACCUUACUGAUUUGCUGCACCAAGGAGACCACAGUCACUCCAGAUCUUAAACAUAUUCAUAAUUGUGUUUGGAGCAAAGUUACCAUUGGAAUCAGAUUUUCACAGUGCUGGUACCGAUCUCUGGGAUCCUCUUGUCCUUUUUUGCAUUUACUCUGCUCUGUUCCUUCUUUCCCACUUAUCUUCCUUUCAGGGUCUCCACUGGCUGUCUUUGCUAACCAAAUAUACAGGAGUUUCCUUGGUCACAAUUAGAAAAUGAGCUUCCAAAAGAAGAGGCACCGAGGGCCCUUGGCACAGGACACAGGAAGGGACUGAUCACGAAUUUAGAUAAUGGGCUGUGUGCAAUGUAAGGAUAAAGAAGCAACAAAACUGACGGAGGAGAGGGACGGCAGCCUGAACCAGAGCUCUGGGUACCGCUAUGGCACAGACCCCACCCCUCAGCACUACCCCAGCUUCGGUGUGACCUCCAUCCCCAACUACAACAACUUCCACGCAGCCGGGGGCCAAGGACUCACCGUCUUUGGAGGUGUGAACUCUUCGUCUCAUACGGGGACCUUGCGUACGAGAGGAGGAACAGGAGUGACACUCUUUGUGGCCCUUUAUGACUAUGAAGCACGGACAGAAGAUGACCUGAGUUUUCACAAAGGAGAAAAAUUUCAAAUAUUGAACAGCUCGGAAGGAGAUUGGUGGGAAGCCCGCUCCUUGACAACUGGAGAGACAGGUUACAUUCCCAGCAAUUAUGUGGCUCCAGUUGACUCUAUCCAGGCAGAAGAGUGGUACUUUGGAAAACUUGGCCGAAAAGAUGCUGAGCGACAGCUAUUGUCCUUUGGAAACCCAAGAGGUACCUUUCUUAUCCGCGAGAGUGAAACCACCAAAGGUGCCUAUUCACUUUCUAUCCGUGAUUGGGAUGAUAUGAAAGGAGACCAUGUCAAACAUUAUAAAAUUCGCAAACUUGACAAUGGUGGAUACUACAUUACCACCCGGGCCCAGUUUGAAACACUUCAGCAGCUUGUACAACAUUACUCAGAGAGAGCUGCAGGUCUCUGCUGCCGCCUAGUAGUUCCCUGUCACAAAGGGAUGCCAAGGCUUACCGAUCUGUCUGUCAAAACCAAAGAUGUCUGGGAAAUCCCUCGAGAAUCCCUGCAGUUGAUCAAGAGACUGGGAAAUGGGCAGUUUGGGGAAGUAUGGAUGGGUACCUGGAAUGGAAACACAAAAGUAGCCAUAAAGACUCUUAAACCAGGCACAAUGUCCCCCGAAUCAUUCCUUGAGGAAGCGCAGAUCAUGAAGAAGCUGAAGCACGACAAGCUGGUCCAGCUCUAUGCAGUGGUGUCUGAGGAGCCCAUCUACAUCGUCACCGAGUAUAUGAACAAAGGAAGUUUACUGGAUUUCUUAAAAGAUGGAGAAGGAAGAGCUCUGAAAUUACCAAAUCUUGUGGACAUGGCAGCACAGGUGGCUGCAGGAAUGGCUUACAUCGAGCGCAUGAAUUAUAUCCAUAGAGAUCUGCGAUCAGCAAACAUUCUAGUGGGGAAUGGACUCAUAUGCAAGAUUGCUGACUUCGGAUUGGCCCGAUUGAUAGAAGACAAUGAGUACACAGCAAGACAAGGUGCAAAGUUCCCCAUCAAGUGGACGGCCCCCGAGGCAGCCCUGUACGGGAGGUUCACAAUCAAGUCUGACGUGUGGUCUUUUGGAAUCUUACUCACAGAGCUGGUCACCAAAGGAAGAGUGCCAUACCCAGGCAUGAACAACCGGGAGGUGCUGGAGCAGGUGGAGCGAGGCUACAGGAUGCCCUGCCCGCAGGACUGCCCCAUCUCUCUGCAUGAGCUCAUGAUCCACUGCUGGAAAAAGGACCCUGAAGAACGCCCCACUUUUGAGUACUUGCAGAGCUUCCUGGAAGACUACUUUACCGCGACAGAGCCCCAGUACCAACCUGGUGAAAACCUGUAAGGCCCGGGUCUGCGGAGAGAGGCCUUGUCCCAGAGGCUGCCCCACCCCUCCCCAUUAGCUUUCAAUUCCGUAGCCAGCUGCUCCCCAGCAGCGGAACCGCCCAGGAUCAGAUUGCAUGUGACUCUGAAGCUGACGAACUUCCAUGGCCCUCAUUAAUGACACUUGUCCCCAAAUCCGAACCUCCUCUGUGAAGCAUUCGAGACAGAACCUUGUUAUUUCUCAGACUUUGGAAAAUGCAUUGUAUCGAUGUUAUGUAAAAGGCCAAACCUCUGUUCAGUGUAAAUAGUUACUCCAGUGCCAACAAUCCUAGUGCUUUCCUUUUUUAAAAAUGCAAAUCCUAUGUGAUUUUAACUCUGUCUUCACCUGAUUCAACUAAAAAAAAAAAAGUAUUAUUUUCCAAAAGUGGCCUCUUUGUCUAAAACAAUAAAAUUUUUUUUCAUGUUUUAACAAAAACCAAUCAGGACAGGUGUUUGUUUUUGUUUUCUUUUUUAUAAAUAUGAAUAUAUAUAAUAUAUAUGUCCCUGUACAUAUACAAUGUGGGUGCUAAUGUGGAGACUGUGGCCGGCCUGAGCCACCAAGCUGCGGGACCCAGAGGGAGGAUUUUACUGCAAGUCAGCAUCAAAGCACCGGUGUUAUUCUGAAAACACCAGUGGCCUCAUUUUUGGCUUUUGCAAAGCAUGAAUUUUUUCAUUUGGAUUGCACUUUCCUGGUUCAUGACUGUACCUGUAGGUGGUUGUUACUUUGACUCUUUUCAGGAACCACCCCCCAAGCUGAAUUUACAAGUUCUGUUAGCACUAUUUGCUUCAACUUACUGCGAUUUGUUCUCAAAACUUAAAAAUAAGCAAGCAAAUGGCUGAUACUACCAAGAGAACUGGAAGAUGGAUACCACACAAACUUCUUGUAUAAAAAUAUGAAUGCUGAAAUGUUUCAGACAUUUUUAAUUUAAUAAACCUGUAACCACAUUUAAGUGAUCUAAAACCCAUAGCAUUGUAGUCAUGGCAACCCGCUAAACUUUCUCAUGCAACUAAAAUUUCUGGGGGAAAUGAGGGUGGGGGUUGUACAUUUCCCAUUGUAAAAUAAGUGUUUUAAAUGUCCUGUACUGCUAACGAAUGACUUUCUAUAUGUCCAGGAGUUCUCCAGUGGAAUAACUAUGCACUACUUUACAUUUCAUGGGGAUGCACAAAAACAAAAAAGUAUUACAUUUUUAGUUGCUGUUUGUACCAACCUUAAAUUACAUAUGUUUAACAACAACAAAUCAAAAAUCCUAUUUCUAUUGAGUUUUUAAUACUGACUAGCAACUCUGAAGUCUUAAUUCCUUUUUUGUUAUGAUUUAUUUGUGAGUUUACAUUUUUAAAUUGUUUAACUUUCUUAAUUUAGUAAUUAAAAAGAGAGCAUUUUACAUUUGAA